CAGAUCUCCAGACUGACCCCAGGGAACGCCCUGGUACGGGGAACCUAGGACUUAACAACUCCAAGGAAGGGAGUGUAGGAGUUGGGGAGGGACAGUGUCCCCAUCUGCAAUUUCCGGUCAUUGACAGGGAUUUUAGGCCCCGCUGAGAGCCAGGGAUGCAUGAAUGCGUGGAGGGAAAUGAGUUGUAAACAGAGUGUAGGGGAACCUGGCAUCUCCAUGCUGCUUUGCUGCAGCUAAUAUGUUUUGCACCCGGGGUACAUCAUUUUACCUCUGUAAGCCUCAAUUUCCUGUCUGUAAAAUGGGAAAAUUAUGCCUAGUGUUCCUGGGAUACUGAGCUGGCUUCUCUGUGAAGCUAAAACCUCACCUCUAUUUUAAGGCCCAGGUGUCUCUGGCCUCCUGCCCUGGAUUAGGGGACUGGCCCCUGGGGUGGUGAAGGUCAGGGCCCCAGCCCCCAACCACAGUGCUGGGGGAGCUGUACCAAGCCUAGGCCACCCUCGCUCUGGAUGGCAACUUGAAAGCAGAAAAGAUGAGUAGUUUCAUAGGACCUGUGGGGUUGGAUUUCGCAUGCAGAAAAUGAACAACGAAGUGGUGGACAAGGGCUGUGGAGACCUUGGUGCCAGUGGCCCAGCCCUCCAAACACCUGCUGUCUUGGAGGCAAUUCUGUGGGGUGACCUGGUGGCCCCAGUGUCAGGCUGCUGUGUGAUGAGGGAGCUGCUGUUGGAGUAGAACAGGUCAGCAUUAAUUAAGGCCGUACCCUUCUGUCCCUGCUGUUCCCUCUGCCAGUUAGGGGGCUCCACCUUAGAGGCCCCCAGGGAGGGCUGGUUCAAUGCUAGGAUGGAGAGGGUGGCAGGGAGAGGCUUCGUGGUGGGGAAGGCAUUGGAGAUGGGUCUAGGGGAGUGGACAGGCUUUUGUCUGGGGUAGACUAUUCAGGGAGAGGGUACAGCGUGAAUAAAGGCUUGGGGUCCGAGAUGGAAAAAGUGCUUGGUGCAUUCAGGGAGAGGCACUCGGGAAGGAUAAACGGAGGCUAUGGAAGGAGAGGCAAGAGGGGAGCGGUCCUUGGGCGCGAUCCUGGAGGGACAAGAACGUUCCCAGCAGCUUGGGCCGAUCCUUGGCCCCCGUCCCACACUCCCUCCCCCCACACCCCCGCAGAUGUUCCGGGGAGGCCUCCAGACGCGCGGCCACACACCUGUGGCGCCGCCCGCGGGCCCUGACCGCGCCGUCUUUUUCUUUUAAAGGAGCCCUGAAAACCAUACUCUCUGGAUCGCGAGAGCGAGGCCAGGGCCCGCCAAGGGCGUGUGCGCAGGGCGGGGGUCGGCGGGGCUGGGCGGGUGGGGGGCGGGGGGCGGGGUGGGAGAUCGGAAGGGAAGCGCUUCCUGGUUCGAGCCGAGAGGGGCGAAUCCGGCUUCGCUCCGCGCCGCCGGGAGGAGCUGUCUGCAGCCCCCUCCUCCCGCCCUCGCCUCUCCCUCCUCCUUCUCCCGCCCUCCUCGCCGAUCCGGGCGGUGCUGGCAGCCGGAGCGGCGGCGGGCGGGCCGAGCAGCCGGGGCAGCCGCGCGUGGGCAUCCACGGGCGCCGAGCCUCCGUCCGUGUCUCUAUCCCUCCCGGGCCUUUGUCAGCGCGCCCGCUGGGAGCGGGGCCGAGAGCGCCGGUUCCAGUCAGACAGCCCCGCAGGUCAGCGGCCGGGCCGAGGGCGCCAGAGGGGGCCAUGUCGUACCAGGGCAAGAAGAGCAUCCCGCACAUCACGAGUGACCGACUCCUCAUCAAAGGUGGACGGAUCAUCAACGAUGACCAAUCCCUUUAUGCUGACGUCUACCUGGAGGAUGGACUUAUCAAACAAAUAGGAGAGAACUUAAUCGUUCCUGGUGGAGUGAAGACCAUUGAAGCCAACGGGCGGAUGGUUAUUCCCGGAGGUAUUGAUGUCAACACGUACCUGCAGAAGCCCUCCCAGGGGAUGACUGCGGCUGAUGACUUCUUCCAAGGGACCAGGGCGGCACUGGUGGGCGGGACCACGAUGAUCAUUGACCAUGUUGUUCCUGAACCUGGGUCCAGCCUACUGACCUCUUUCGAGAAGUGGCACGAAGCAGCUGACACCAAAUCCUGCUGUGAUUACUCCCUCCACGUGGACAUCACAAGCUGGUACGAUGGCGUUCGGGAGGAGCUGGAGGUGCUGGUGCAGGACAAAGGCGUCAAUUCCUUCCAAGUCUACAUGGCCUAUAAGGAUGUCUACCAAAUGUCCGACAGCCAGCUCUAUGAAGCCUUUACCUUCCUUAAGGGCCUGGGAGCUGUGAUCUUGGUCCAUGCAGAAAAUGGAGAUUUGAUAGCUCAGGAACAAAAGCGGAUCCUGGAGAUGGGCAUCACGGGUCCCGAGGGCCAUGCCCUGAGCAGACCUGAAGAGCUGGAGGCCGAGGCGGUGUUCCGGGCCAUCACCAUUGCGGGCCGGAUCAACUGCCCUGUGUACAUCACCAAGGUCAUGAGCAAGAGUGCAGCCGACAUCAUCGCUCUGGCCAGGAAGAAAGGGCCCCUAGUUUUUGGAGAGCCCAUUGCCGCCAGCCUGGGGACCGAUGGCACCCAUUACUGGAGCAAGAACUGGGCCAAGGCUGCGGCGUUCGUGACUUCCCCUCCCCUGAGCCCGGACCCUACCACGCCCGACUACUUGACCUCCCUACUGGCCUGUGGGGACUUGCAGGUCACAGGCAGCGGCCACUGUCCCUACAGCACUGCCCAGAAGGCGGUGGGCAAGGACAACUUUACCCUGAUCCCCGAGGGUGUCAACGGGAUAGAGGAGCGGAUGACGGUCGUCUGGGACAAGGCGGUGGCUACUGGCAAAAUGGAUGAGAACCAGUUUGUCGCUGUCACCAGCACCAAUGCAGCCAAGAUCUUUAACCUGUACCCAAGGAAAGGGCGGAUUGCCGUGGGCUCGGAUGCCGACGUGGUCAUCUGGGACCCCGACAAGUUGAAGACCAUAACAGCCAAAAGUCACAAGUCGGCGGUGGAGUACAACAUCUUCGAGGGUAUGGAGUGCCACGGCUCCCCACUAGUGGUCAUCAGCCAGGGCAAGAUCGUCUUUGAAGACGGAAACAUCAACGUCAACAAGGGCAUGGGCCGCUUCAUUCCGCGGAAGGCGUUCCCGGAGCACCUGUACCAGCGCGUCAAAAUCAGGAAUAAGGUUUUUGGAUUGCAAGGGGUUUCCAGGGGCAUGUAUGACGGUCCUGUGUACGAGGUACCAGCUACACCCAAAUAUGCAACUCCCGCUCCUUCAGCCAAAUCUUCGCCUUCUAAACACCAGCCCCCACCCAUCAGAAACCUCCACCAGUCCAACUUCAGCUUAUCAGGUGCCCAGAUAGAUGACAACAAUCCCAGGCGCACCGGCCACCGCAUCGUGGCGCCCCCUGGUGGCCGCUCCAACAUCACCAGCCUCGGUUGAACGUGGAUGCGCGGAGGAGCUAGCCUGAAGGAUUCUGGGAAUCAUGUCCAUCCCUUUUCCUGUCAGUGUUUUUGAAACCCACAGUUUUAGUUGGUGCUGAUGGAGGGAGGGGGAAGUCGAAGGAUGCUCUUUCCCUUUUCUGUUUAGGAAGAAGUGGUACUAGUGUGGUGUGUUUGCUUGGAAAUUCCUUGCCCCACAGUUGUGUUCAUGCUGAAUCCACCUCGGAGCAUGGUGUUUUCAUUCCCCCUUCCUAGUGAACCACAGGUUUUAGCAUUGUCUUGUUCUGUCCCUUCCACUUCUAACUCCACUGGCUCCAUGAUUCUCUGAGUGGUGGUUCCUUUGCACCCUGUAGAUGUUCUAGGAUAGUUGAUGCAUGUUACUAAAUUACGUAUGCAAGUCUGUGAGUGCGUCUGAGGGGACAUCGCCAAGGACUGACUGAGACACGAUGCCGAGACCUCAAGCCCUGAGGGGCAGUCCCAAAACCCUUACAGUGAAGAUGUUUACUCAUUGCCCCCACCUCUGGUCCACACUAGAAAGAAGCUCGCCCCACCUCCACCUGUGAGAUCCGUGAAUUCUCGGAAUGGCAGGGGAAGCCUUGCACUAGGUUGCAGAGAAGCAUCCUCCACAUCCUGUGUCAGAAACCCUGGUCUCCGUGGCACUUGUAACUCACCGUGCUGUCUUCUGGUCUGUGUGUGUUCUUCAAGCCAGCUCUAGGCUUCAGGCCGAGCCAGGUUCACACUCAGAAAGAGGUCUCCCCAUCCCCAUUCGGGGCUGACGAUGGGGGGCUGAUGGCUGCCCCUGCGUGGCCUGAGUCCUGGUCCCUCUGAGGCAGUUGACGGGGCAGUCAGAUUUUUAAAGUUUUGUACAAAGUUUUCCUUUGUAAUCACUCCCAUUUUUACUUAACAACCAACUUGUUGUGGCUCUUAUUUCUGAAUUCAAAGCUUGUGAAAAAAUAAAGAAAAUGAACUGCCCACUGACCUGACUAGGGCACUUUCA